GGCUGAGCUCGGGCUGCGGCUCCGGUGGGGGUGGGUGGCGGGGAUGACAGCGGAGGUGGCAGCGGCGCGGCGCUGAGCGAGCGGCGAGGGAGCAGGGGAAGAGGAGGAAGUGGAGCCGCGGCCGGGAGCUCGGGAGUCGGCCGCCGCGCCGAGGGUCGCUCCGCGCCUUUCCGUCAGUGAGGGUCGGAACCCCAGCUCCAGGGCUAGCGCAGUGUGGCCCCAGGCCCUCGCCUCCGGUGCACGGGACCCCGGACCCCCCCAGCCUCUGGCUUCACGAGACCCCAACCUUCAGUUGGAACAGCUUGGAACAGCGCGAGCGCCCGGGAAGCCCUGGCCGGGUCGUGCGCUCGGUGAGGGGUCCUAGGCGGGCAGGACAGUCGGACCGAACCGCCGGGCUGGUGCCGCGAGCCCAGGCUGUCACCUUCGUCCCGCCUCAGGUGAGGGGUUCAGCGCCUGCCCCGAAGAUAACACAGGGGUCCCCUUCUGUCCCGGCGGCCUGCGAGAGCCAAGGCUGCAGGCUGGAGUGCAAUGGCGCGAUCUUCACUCACUGCAGCCUCCGCCUCCCAGGUUCAAGCGAUUCUCCUGCCUCAGCCUCCCAAGUAGCUGGGAUUACAGGCAAGUGCCACCACACGCAGCUAAUUUUGUAUUUUUAGUAGAGAUGGAGUUUCGCUAUGUUGGUUAGGCUGGUCUCAAACUCCUGACUUCAGGUGAUCCGCCUGCCUCAGCCUCCCAAAGUGCUGGGAUUAUAGCUGUGAGCUACCGCCCCCCAGCCUAAAAGCUUGCAAUUUCUAUAGCAUUUUCACUUAGCACCUCCCCCAACAACUUCCACCUAGCAACCUCCAUUUACCCCAAACCACAGACCUCAAUCCUCUGUUUGGCCCGCAAGUUCCAUAGGAUGGGCCAAGAGCUCAGAUGUUCCUCAUAGAUAAGGAGUGGAUCUCCGGGUUGGCUACUCCCAGAUUCCUUAGCUUAGAACCAAACUGCAUUGAGGUGCGCCUGCCAUACAAGGUCAUUCUCAGGGCUUGCUCAAGUCCAGGUAUCACUGUCCAACGUGUCUACCAUACAGAAGACAGAAAACUUAUGUUGAUCCUGGCUUUGUCACUUACUGGCAGGAUGACCCUGGAAGAAUCAUUUUAUCUCUUUGAGCACGAGUUGUUUCUCCUAUAAAAUGCAUUUGUAGGAAGGACUUCCUGGGAUUACCUGAGAAGCAAAUAAAAUUACUGGUAUGUGGAGCACAGUGCCUACCGUAAACUAAGCACUCAAGAGCUGUUGGUGCAUGCACUUGCUGGGGAGCUGACCCCUGCCUCCUGCCCCUUCCUUCACUGGCUGGUCCACGCUCCCUGUCUCCCAGUCUGCUCCCCUUGCCCCACCAGGCCCAGGCUGAGACAGAGGACAGAGGAGGCCUGCACAUGUAAUCAUGGGCAUCCCUUCAAACUGCUCUUCUUUAAGACCAGAGGAGGCUCUGAGGACUGGACAGAGGAAGACUACAAAAGGGGCCAUCAGUGGCAGUGCUUGGUCUCCUUGCCUGGGCACAGCCAGAGAGGGUACAUCAACCCAGAGUGACUGGCUCAGGCAUUAGGCGUGUGACAAAUCAACACGGGAUAGUGCAGCACCGAGGGACUAGCAGUGGCUGGGAGCAGUUACCACUCAGGGCUGAAGGAGCAAGGGAAGUGGGCAGCUAUAGGGAUAGGGGCUGUGGGCCAUCAGUACAGGGACCCAGUCAACCCAGGAGACCUCACAGGGGAUAAACUUCAACUAUCUUUCCUCUUUCCUUCAGUCCCCCAUUUAUGCUUCCUGUUGGGUGUACCUCUCUGAAAGCCAGCAGCAUGGAGCCCAUUACAUUCCACAGAGGUCAGUUCCCAGGGCCCCAAACAAGGUAGAGAGUGGCUCUGGAGAAGCAAACCAAAGACACUUCCUCACUCUGUCCAUCAAAAGCCCGGGAGUCCACUGAAUACACUGUCCUUAGGACACAGUUUAAAGAUCAUCUGUUUUUACCAUACCCCUUAAUGAAGGGGCUCUCAGCCCUUACCCCAAAGAUGAAUCAGCAGCCGAGCUGCCACAGACACCUCGGCGAGAGGAGUUUUGGAGGUACCCAUCUCUCCCUCUCUGCCUCCUCCACCAAAGUAAGCUAUAGAUGGCUUCUGGGGUGACCCUGCCAGGGACAGGGGAACCUCUGGAGUGGAGCAGAAGUCACAGGUAGGCUAGUGUCAGGCGAGUUCAGGUGCACAGAGCAGCGGCCCCAGCCCUGCUGCGACUUGCCCAUCCCAGAGCUGGCCAUGAUGUGGCCACUUCACACACCUUCCUUAGAGCUGGGCAGUCAUUGCCACAGUUCUGGGGAUAGCCCUGGACCCAGAACAUGUUCCUCAUGUCCAGGGUGUUAAGAGCCAUGCCACUCUGAGUUCAGAGGGUCUCCCAGGAGCCUAUGAAUGUCAGGUAAGAGGAGCGUGGGGCUGGGCAGGCCUGGGACAGGCCGUGCAGCAAGUGCCACCAAAUGCUGCCAGGCCUUGUGAUGGGGAGUCUGGGUGUGGAGUUAGGUGGGGGGUGUGGUUCUUGCCAGGCAGGGAGCAGGAGGCAUAAUGGUGCCAGAGACUGAGCCUUGCCCAAGAGGAGGCAUGGUCAGGGAGAGGACAGAAGAUAUGACACUUUGCAUGGAAACCAUGUGGGAGGCCCCCACGGGGUGUUGUCUGCAGGGGCACAGCCGGCAGGUCUAGGACACAGAGCCCUUUACAGCUGGCUGCCAGCGAGCACUCCCUCUCCUUCCUGAAAGGAAUGCCCCUGGCAUCUCCACCAGCUCACACCUAGGCAUCUGAGGUGACACAGUGAGAUGCCCAUGGCAGGUGUGGUAACACCUGGAUCCUCAGAGACUUCCUGAGAAGGGAGGUAUGUGGGCCUCGGAGUCAGAAUUCUGGCUUGGAAUCCUGGCUCUGCCUCUCUUGAGUGGAACUUAGAAGACAUGGGCAAGUCACUUAGCCUCUCUGAGCCUCAGUUGCUCACCUAUAAAAUUAGAGCAGCAACACUUACCUUCCAGGCUGGUUUGAAAGUAAAAUGACAUAAUGAAUGAGACAGCAUCCUGUAUUUCAGAGGAGAUGCUACAGUUGCCCUCAUCAUGCCCCCCUUCUCUGUAUGCUGUUCAUGCUUAAUGCCUCUGCAGGAAGUUCUUUCUUGAGACUAAUUGAAGUCCACUCUGCUGCAAUUGGAGCCUUCUUCCUCUUGCUGGGGACUCUGCAGAGGCAGACUGAGCCCCUCCUCUGUCCAGAUGUGCCCUGUCAGUGCCUGCAGUGAGUGAAGCAGAGAACUGGGUGACCAGGUGUUGAUUUUCACCUUGGAGCUUGGGGGUUCAACUGUCAAUGGCCAGAGCCUCUUGACCAUGGCAGGAUAGGGGGUGCAUCAUCCUAACUCUUCACACUGUUCUUCCUCUCUGUGCUUAAUGCAUGCUCCAAAAGGGGUGACUUUGGGCCCGUGCAGAGAGCCCUGGGCUGGGCCUAAAGGCCUGGGUCCUGGCACCUCCGUCUCACUGUGUGGCCCAAGGCCAGUUAGCAACCAUUUCGGGCCACCGUGGGCCUGCAAGGAUGUCUGUGCUCUAGGGCCCAGGUCCCUCCAGUGAAGACAUAUGUAGUUCUGACUGAAGACCCUUCUCCUGCUUCUCCCCCUCUGGGACCCUAGCCAACCUGGGAAGACAGCAGAUAGGGUCCUGCUGGUGGCUGGCAGUGGUAGCAGCUGAGUCCAUCUCUCAGACCAGGACUGCCAAGGGCAGGCCGAGAAUUCAAGGUUAGAUGGGUGAUUCCUGGUAGGUAGGGUUUUGCCUCCCUCCUCAAAACAGAGCCUGGUGCUCCCCUUCCUACCCACUCAGCUGAACUCACCCAGCUCAAGGGCAGUCAUGUUUGAGUCUCUCCUUGGAGUGGCUCCUUUCCCACAUGAGAUCCGCUUUCAUCCCUCAUUUUGCAGGUGAGAAACCUCGGGCUCAGGCAGGUGAGGUGACUGGCUUGAGGUCCCACAGCCUGUCGGUGGGAAGUGGUGAGGGUCCCUGCGGCAGCUCCCAUGGCACCUGGGCCAGGCCGUGCCCUCUAGGUCCUCAGCAGGAGUGGAGCACAGGAGAGUCAGGAGGCUACUAGCCAGGUGGUCUCCUGGUCUAGGAGGAGGCCCUAUGGGUGCCAGGGGAACCCUGCUCUGUGGGCCUUGAGGGGUCAUCUGGGGCUCCUGGGAUUGCUGGGUCCCUUUCCCUGGGAGGAAGUUAGCCGAGGAAUGCCAGAGGUUGAGAGCGAGGAACCCAGGAGUUCUAGGCUGUGACUAGUUCUGAGUGCCCCUGUAAACUUCAGUGUUUAGUUUCACGGAGAGUCAAGACUGACUUUUUGUUGACUUUGGACACAUGACAGUUUAACUUUACGAAGCGCUCUGAUAUCUGUGAUGUCAUUGCAUCCUCACAGCAGUCUGUGAGGAGGAAGUGUGGGACUUGUUUGGGAGGGCAGGAGAGUGUGGGCUCUGGAAUCAGACACACCGGAGCUUACACCCUGACUCCCACCGGCUCUCUGACCUCAGGCAAGUUGGUAACCAGCCAAGUCUCAGUUUGCUCAUCUGUGAAAGGGACAAUUUACUCCACAACAAAUUGUUAGCAACACCUGCCUUGCUGGCUGUGUGCCUUAAGAGAACAUCUGUAACUGCUGGGUCAGUGUCUGGUGCCAUGUAAUAGUUUUCAUGAUUUUUAUCAGACCCACUUUAUAGAAGGGAAGAUGGAGGCUGAGAGAAGGAAGGUGACUUGUCUGAGGUCAUGUAAUGAUUUAAAUUGGUCCUCCAGACUUCUUGUCUGUGAAUUUUUUCUAUAAAACCUCCCUCUCCAUCCUCAAGUGACCCGAUACCUCAUUUAUCCAGAACCCUCCACGUGUGAUGCUGUCUAGACGUGGCAUUGUGUCCCCAGUGCCCAACAGCACUUGCCUGGUACACAGUAUGUCCUGUGCAUAGAUGUGUUGAUGAAUUCAUAUAAACUGUAAGAAACAUUUUUCCAGAAGAAGCAGCUAAGGCCUGUGUCUUGCCCUAAAGACUUCUUUCUUUCUUUCUUUUUUGAGACAGAGUUUCGCUCUUGUUGCCCAGGCUGCAACCUCUGCCUCCCAGGUUCAAGUGAUUCUCCUGCCUCGGCCUCCCACAUAGCUGGGAUUACAGGUGCCCGCCACCACGCCCAGCUAAUUUUGUAUUUUUAGUAGAGACAGGGUUUCAUCAUGUUGGUCAGUCUGGUCUGGAACUCCUGACCUCAGGUGAUCCACCUGCCUCGGCCUCCCAAAGUGCUGGGAUUACAGGAGUGAGCCACCACACCCAGCUCUAAAGACUUCUUUCUGCUCUCUAUCCCAUUAAAAACAACUCUAACAGUUUUGGUUGGAAACCUUUGCAAAAGAGAUUGAUCACUUUCUUCCUCUGAACAAUGGCAACAUGGACGGGUUGAGGGACAGGCCUUAGGAACCCCGCCUGCCUUGCUGAGAAUGCCGACGCGGCUUGACCCCUGUGCCAGAUGACCCUGGGCUGCUGCAUGUGUUCAACUCUGGUUUCUGGCUCUUCCCACCCUGUCGGUUCCUUUAUUCUGCUGCCCACAGACUUGCCUCCAGAGCGCUGCAUCUCUUUCCUCUCCCCUCGUGUGUGUGUGUGUGUGUGUGUGUGUGUGUGUGUGUGUGUGUGUCCUUCCCAAUUUCAUGCUUCUACCAGUUAGGGACUAAGAAAUGGAACAAUUGACCUUACUAGAAUUGGUUCGUGUAUUCAUUCAUACCUAUUCAACCAGUCAGCCAUUGGUGAGCCUGUGUCACACUGGGGAUUCUGUCUGUGCAUUCUUCCAUGCAUCCAUGUAUCCAUCCAUCCAUCUGUCCUGAUUGAGGACCUCUGCAGUGGCUUGUGAUCAAUCAAGACAUUACCACACCCUCCUGGCCAUGCAUGCAGUAAAAUAAUGAUGCACACAGCAAAUGCUGGCACAGGACUUGACAGUUUGUAAUCUGCCUCUGCUUGCAUUACCUCAAUCUUCACAACAGCCCUGAGAAUAGCAUUAUCCCCAUUUUGCAGAUGAUGAAAACAAAGCUUAGCAGGAUGGGGUCCCCCCGCCCAAUGGCCAGCAGUGAGCACAAAGUCACAGUUGGAACUCACUCAGGUCUCUGGCCCACUCUGUUACCUUCUCCCUCCUUUGCGCUACGUUUGGAGGCUGUCUGAUGCCAUGUUCAUUAUCUGUCUCUGUCAUGAGCUAUUGGUGGUGGUGGCUGAGGUUGGACUUUUUGCCUCUGUCAAAUGGUCAGUGCAGGGAAGCAUGGCCCUGGCUGGGUGGCAGCCACAGACACCCUUCAACCUGCAGACCUUGUCCCGCCUGGACCCAGGCGCACUAUCUAGUCCACACUCCCCAAACUGUCCCCUGAGGAGCCCUAGUCCCGUGGCAUGGGAAUGGAUUCAAGGAUGCAUGAGCAUACAGAUUUGGGAAACGCUAGGUCACAUAAAUCCAAACAGGCCUUCUCAGGGUCUUUAAUGUAUUAAUACGAAUUAGGGACCCCAAUGGGUGGCAGAGUGUGCAGCCAGCCUUUCCUAAGCUUAUUUGAACAUGCAACUCCUUGGUCAAAGAGCAGGGUCUGGACACACCGUCUUGAGAAUGCAGUGAGAAGAUCUCAUGGGCAAACCCUGACCUUGCUGUUUUGUGCAAGGAAACCCCCAGCCAGAGCUAGUUUCCUGGCCCAGGACUGCAUUUUGAGAGAGCAUCACAGGGAAUACUCUUUAGCCCCAGAAAAGAUUCAGUGAUAAUGGUGGAACUUCAGGCAGCAGGGGCAAGUGGCCGUGGAGAUAUUUUUAUUCUUUCAUCCACCAAAAGAACAUAUCUCAGACAUCUACUGUGUGCCAGGAACAGAGCCAGCACUUGGAAAUGCCAAGACAAUCUAAGUCUCUUCCAUUUCAUUUUUCCCCCACAGUGCUGCAUCUCUUUCCUCCGAGGGUUUUCAAAGAAAGACAAGCCUUAAAUACAUGCCUUAAAAGGAAGAAGUGAUCUGUUAAUUGCUCUGGGUCGUUGCUUUGGGUGGGUGACACAUUUACUCAAUUCAGCGGAGCUGUACCUUCUUAGUCCCAGGUCCUGAGGGGCAGAGAGUGAGGCAAUUCCAGGACCCAUUACCCUGGGCAGAGUGCACAGAUGUUGCAAGGGAGGUCAAGAGCAUGGGGAGGCCCGGAGGAGGAGGAGGGGGGAGGGGGAGAAGGGAGCGAGCUUCCUCCUGGGGUCCAUCAGUCUCAGCUUGGGGUUGGGGGGCACUUAAGUGAGGCUCUGCGAAGAAGAGAUGGGGGAGUGGGGGUGGAUGGGCUCCAGGUGGCUGGGAAGGGCAUUCUUCCAACAGCUGGAGCAGAGGUGAAAGGAGGCAGCACAUGACACUGUGUCAUGAGGACCCUGUAAGGAGCCUGUGGAUGUGGGAGCAGAGGGAGGAAAAGGAGGUCAGACGGGGCUGGAGAAGUUUCUGGGGCAGAUUUUGAGGGUCUGAGCUCCAGCCAAGUGGGUGCUUACCUGAUGAGGAGCCUCUUCAGAGCUGGUCACAUUCAUCCCAGUGUCCCCAGCACCUGGCUGGUGCCCAGUGGGUGUUUGUGGACUGGCUGGACUCUUCCUCUGUAGGCCUCGGGUUCCUCACAUUUGUGGUCAGGCGAGGUCACCUGGCACCUCCCUUCCUACUCUGAAGAGCUCUCAGGAGUUCUGGAUGCUUGUGCAGGGGAAGGCCUCACCACUCUCCCUGUCUCCUGCCUCAGGGUUCUCUGGGUUGCCCCAGCAGGGCUGGGGCCAUGGUGCCCUGAGUGGGGGACAGCCCUCCCGCUGCCAGGGAACUUUGCCCCUCGUGCUUUCUCCCUUCAGCAGUUGGCCCCCUGAGCCCAGAAGGACAUUCCUUGGUGUCCCGUGACUGGGAGUGGCAGUGGCAUUGAGCGCAUGCUGCAGCUUAGCACGGGGAGGGAGCUCUGCUUCCAUCUAUGUGAAAAUGGGCAGCCAGGUGUGGUAGCUCAUGCCUAUAAUCCCAACACUUUGGGAGGCCGAGGCGGGCAGAUCACUUGAGGUCAGGAGUUCGAGACCAGCCUGGCCAACAUGGUGAAACCCUGUCUCUACUAAAAAUACAAAAAUUAGCCGGGCUUGGUGGUGCGUGCCUGUAAUCCCAGCUCCUCGGGAGGCUGAGGCAGGAGAAUCGCUGGAACCCAGGAGGCGGAGAUUGCAGUGAGCUGAGAUCGUGCCACUGCACUCCAGCCUGGGCAACAGAGCAAGACUCCAUCUCAAAAAAGAAAAAGAAAAUGGGCAAGUGACUCAGCCUCUGAGCCUCCGCCUUCUUGUCUGUUAAUAGUAACUUCCACACUGGACUUUUAUGAAGGUUCAACGAGAUAAAGUUUGAACAUGGAUUAUAAACUGACUUACUCCACAAACAAGUAAACAGUUCUUGGCAUUAACAAUAUUCAUUUGUCCAAUUUAUAUUAAUCCCCCAAGCCUCUGGGCCACUCACCUCUUUUCAGGAAGUGCUCCCUGGCAUCAGCUCACUGUUCUCUGUGCAAGCUGCCCCUGCUGGUACAUUUUAUCCAGGCCAGAGCAAUAGGAGCCUCUGAAUUAUGUACAAGUCGCACACACAGGCCAGAACUGUGUGUCUGCAGCCCUGUCUGUGUUUGAACAGAAAGAAAGAUGGUGCUGUCCUUCCUAUCUGCUGGGCCCAGGGACCAGAUACCGCCCCUUCCCUGGCUGCAACCCAGGGGUCUCGGCCUCUGAGGAAGGCUGGGAGCACAUGUCAAGAACACCCCCCACACCCAACUUGUCUGUCCUGUUUACAGUCUGGGUCUAACAUGACCUGCCCACAUACAGGAGCCUCUCUGUGUCCUGCAUCCCUGGGUGGCUGGUGGGCAUAGGGCUUGAGGGGCAGAAAAAGACAGUCACUCCACAUCCCUUCCACUUCCCUGUUCAUGCCAGGAGCUGUCAGUCGGGAUGACCAAGAUCUUCAAUGUGGACACUGCUUUAUUUCAGCAGGGCCUCAGGUACCCCCUCUGGGAGGCCUGCAGCCUGUCACAGCAUGCUGAGCCAAAGCCACCUGCCCAGGUUCCCAAAUCUUGGAAGCACUGGAUCAUGGAACCAUAGAAUCUCGGUGAUAUGAAAUCCAGACUUGGAGGAGGCCUAAGGGGUCACAAUCCAAACCUUCAUCCAGCCCAGGCAGCCCCUCUGCAGGCUCCGUGAACACUCUGGCAACUGGGGAGUCAUCUGUAGCCCCCUCAGCUCUCCCAGUGAAGUGAUAUCACUGCCUCUGUGGACAAGACACCUCCAGGAGCCCAGCUCACAGCCACCGGUACCUUCUUCCAGGGCUGCUGUUAUAGUUUCUGCAUGGAAAGCACUUGGAACAAUGCCUGGCUGUUCCCCUCUUUGGCCCUCUCAGGGCCCUAGGAGCCUUUGUGUGUCCUGCUCACAUUGUCUCCAGGGCCUCGGACAGGGCCUGGUACAGAACAUAUGACUGAGUUUCUGGAGUCCCACAGGCCAGCGUUGGAGUCCUGACACCUCAGUAUAGCUGUGCACCUCUGGGCAAAUAGUUUCUCUGCUCUGAGCCCCAGGACAAGCUGGGGGCCUCCAUGGGCGCCUGAGGGCCAGGCGCCAGGGCCGUGGGCACGAGUAUGGUGAGACACCAGCCCCUGCAGUACUACGAGCCACAGCUGUGCCUCUCCUGCCUCACGGGCAUCUACGGCUGCCGUUGGAAGCGCUACCAGCGCUCCCAUGAUGAUACCACACCGUGGGAGCGCCUCUGGUUCCUGCUCCUCACCUUCACCUUUGGCCUCACGCUCACCUGGCUUUACUUCUGGUGGGAAGUCCACAAUGACUAUGAUGAAUUCAACUGGUACCUCUACAACCGCAUGGGCUACUGGAGCGACUGGCCCGUACCCAUCCUUGUGACCACAGCUGCUGCCUUCGCAUACAUCGCUGGCCUCCUGGUCCUGGCACUAUGUCACAUUGCCGUGGGGCAGCAGAUGAACCUGCACUGGCUGCACAAGAUCGGGCUGGUGGUCAUCCUGGCUUCCACGGUGGUGGCCAUGUCGGCCGUGGCCCAGCUGUGGGAGGACGAGUGGGAGGUGCUGCUGAUCUCCCUGCAGGGCACAGCGCCAUUCCUGCAUGUGGGGGCUGUGGCAGCAGUCACCAUGCUCUCCUGGAUCGUGGCAGGACAGUUCGCCCGCGCAGAGCGGACCUCCUCCCAGGUGACCAUUCUCUGUACCUUCUUCACCGUGGUGUUUGCCCUCUACCUGGCCCCUCUCACCAUCUCCUCUCCCUGCAUCAUGGAGAAGAAAGACCUCGGCCCCAAGCCUGCUCUCAUUGGCCACCGCGGGGCCCCCAUGCUGGCUCCAGAGCACACGCUCAUGUCCUUCCGGAAGGCCCUCGAGCAGAAGCUGUACGGGCUCCAGGCUGACAUUACCAUCAGCCUGGACGGCGUGCCCUUCCUCAUGCAUGACACCACCCUGCGGCGCACCACCAACGUGGAGGAGGAGUUCCCGGAGCUGGCCCGCAGGCCUGCCUCCAUGCUUAACUGGACCACCCUGCAGAGACUCAACGCUGGCCAGUGGUUCCUGAAGACUGACCCCUUCUGGACAGCCAGCUCCCUGUCACCCUCCGACCACAGAGAGGCCCAGAACCAGUCCAUCUGCAGCCUGGCAGAGCUCCUGGAGCUGGCCAAGGGCAAUGCCACACUGCUGCUCAACCUGCGUGACCCGCCCCGGGAGCACCCCUACCGCAGCAGUUUUAUCAACGUGACUCUGGAGGCCGUGCUGCACUCCGGCUUCCCCCAGCACCAGGUCAUGUGGCUGCCUAGCAGGCAGAGGCCCCUGGUGCGGAAGGUGGCUCCCGGCUUCCAACAGACAUCAGGCUCCAAGGAGGCAGUCGCCAGCCUGCGGAGAGGCCACAUCCAGCGGCUGAACCUGCGCUACACUCAGGUGUCCCGCCAGGAGCUCAGGGACUACGCGUCCUGGAACCUGAGUGUGAACCUCUACACAGUCAACGCACCGUGGCUCUUCUCCCUGCUGUGGUGUGCGGGGGUCCCAUCCGUCACCUCUGACAACUCCCACGCCCUGUCCCAGGUGCCUUCCCCCCUCUGGAUCAUGCCCCCGGACGAGUACUGUCUCAUGUGGGUCACUGCCGACCUGGUCUCCUUCACCCUCAUCGUGGGCAUCUUCGUGCUCCAGAAGUGGCGCCUGGGUGGCAUACGGAGCUACAACCCUGAGCAGAUCAUGCUGAGUGCUGCGGUGCGCCGGACCAGCCGGGACGUCAGCAUCAUGAAGGAGAAGCUUAUUUUCUCAGCAGAGAUCAGCGAUGGUGUAGAGGUCUCCGAUGUGCUCUCCGUAUGUUCAGACAACAGUUAUGACACAUAUGCCAACAGCACCGCCACCCCUGUGGGCCCCCGAGGGGGUGGCAGCCACACCAAGACCCUCAUAGAGCGGAGUGGGCGUUAGCUGAAGACAUGUCUGUCCCACCUGUACCUGACACAGAAGCUGGGGAGCCUAGGAGAGCUGGUGGAAGUGUGUCUGAACUCGGAGUGCUCUGGGAGCGGGCUCCACAGCCUCCUUGUGGGCUCCAGCCCCUUGUCAGCCGCAGCCUCUCUUGAGGGGGACUCCCUGUCUCCUGAGGCCCAGCUGGGCCAGGACUCCAUCCUUUCAGAUGCCCCUGCAGGCCUGGGGCUCCUUCUGGGAAGUAUGGGGCCUAGGGCUUGGUCCCCCUCUUCUGAGGCCCUCUCCUGUAUCCCGACCUGGAAGCUUUGAUGGGUCAUGGGCCAUGCCAUACCCCCUGUGGCAAUGGAGUGUGUGGAUGCUCACCUGUGCCAUCUGUCCUCCUGUCUGUGCCAGGAGGCACCUGAGUUCUCUGCUGUUAUCCUGCCCCAAGGGCCUGGGCCGAGCCUCUACCUGAAGCAACUCUGCUCUUCCUGUCAGUCUCAAAGCACAAGGAGGUUCAGCCCAGGAGGAAGCCAGCUGCAAUGUGGAGACACGUCCUCCUCCCCAACCCACCUCAUGCCACCGCCAACCCCCUGCCCCAGGAGCGGGCCUGAGCCACGUCCUCUAGGAGCAGCUGGAGAUGGCCAAAAGAGUGAGCUCAGGACUACUGGAUCCCAUGCCCAGGUGUCCAGCAGACCUCAAGGCAGAAGGGUCACCUAACCCAGGAGUCCACAGACUGAUGUGACCUCAGGUUCCCACAUCAGUGGCCACAGGGCAGGGCCCACCUGGUAGAAGUGUUCUGGAUAUGGCCAGGGUGGGUGUGUGGCUAAGUGGGCCUGAACAGAGGGAACCUAGGGCCCUUGGCCAAUGUGAUUAAAGCUGCCAUCUUGA